UGGCUUCCCACAGUGCUGGGAUUACAGGCAUGGGCCACUGCGCCUGGCCUGAUCUGUUGAUUUCUAAGUGUUAGGUUCUCUGUCAUAAUUUUUAUAUGCAUUAUUUUCUUUUUUCUUCAUAAUAUACUAGAAUAAAUGAUAUUUCUGUUUUAUAGAUUAGGCAUAGAGCAGUUAAGGAACAUGCUUGAGGUCAUUCAUGUUGAGAUCAAUAAGUGAUAGAAGUAUAUUUCAAACUCAGUUCUUUCAAUUAAACUAUUUUCCUGAAAACUGUUUAUCAUCUACAUACUAUGUACACAGCUACUGGAGAAAUAAUACUUGGCCAUGAUGUCUUGAAAAAAGUUGUGAGUGACUUUAUAUUGUAGAGUGUCAUAUAUAAAUAAUCUCAUUUAGGUUUCUUUCAGCUGAUUUAUUUUUGGCAACUUAAUCCUUAAAUUAUAAACUUUCUUACUCUAUAUUGUACCUAUGCCAUAUUUAUUAACCCAGUCUCUGUGAUUCACCAAGUAAUUCUUGAAUAAUUGUGUAGUUGAAAUAUGUUUUCUGUAAGUUACCACAUGCUUUUAGGAGUGAGAAAAAGAAAAGUGGCCGUGAUAUCUAGAAACUGGUAUUGCUAGAAACUAGCCUGGCAUUCACAGUAACUUUGUGUUUUUCUGUUGAAGAUAAACUAUUGUACAGAAUGUCAACAUCAGAUAAGGCCGCUCUGUGUCUAUGAUGGAUCAAGACAAAAACAUUCCAUCAGUGUCUCCAAACACAGACAAAACAAUCUGCAAAAUGGCUGAUAAUUUGGAUGAAUUUAUUGAAGAGCAAAAAGCCAGAUUGGCCGAAGACAAAGCAGAGUUGGAAAGUGAUCCACCUUACAUGGAAAUGAAGGGAAAGUUGUCAGCGAAGCUUUCUGAAAACAGUAAGAUACUGAUCUCUAUGGCUAAGGAAAACAUACCACCAAAUAGUCAACAGACCAGGGGUUCCUUAGGAAUUGAUUAUGGAUUAAGUUUACCACUUGGAGAAGACUAUGAACGGAAGAAACAUAAAUUAAAAGAAGAAUUGCGGCAAGAUUACAGACGUUAUCUUACUCAGAAAAAUUUUCUAUCUACGAGUGAAACAGAUCCAUCUACUUUGGGAGUUUCUCUUCCUAUUGGUGAGAGGUUAUCUGCUAAGGAAAGGUUGAAACUUGAACGUAACAAAGAAUACAAUCAGUUUCUCAGGGGUAAGGAAGAAUCCAGUGAAAAGUUCAGGCAGGUGGAAAAGAGUACUGAGCCCAAGAGUCAGAGAAAUAAAAAACCUAUUGGUCAAGUUAAGCCUGAUCUAACUUCACAAAUACAGACAUCUUGUGAAAAUUCAGAGGGUCCUAGAAAAGAUGUCUUAACUCCUUCAGAGGCAUAUGAAGAACUUCUGAACCAAAGACGACUAGAGGAGGACAGAUACCGACAACUAGAUGAUGAAAUCGAAUUAAGGAAUAGAAGAAUUAUUAAAAAAGCAAAUGAAGAAGUGGGCAUUUCCAACCUAAAACAUCAAAGGUUUGCAAGCAAGGCUGGCAUUCCAGAUAGAAGAUUUCACAGAUUUAAUGAGGAUCGUGUUUUUGAUAGACGGUAUCAUAGACCAGACCAAGAUCCUGAAGUAAGUGAAGAAAUGGAUGAGAGGUUUAGAUAUGAAAGUGAUUUUGAUAGAAGACUUUCGAGAGUGUAUACAAAUGACAGGAUGCACAGGAACAAACGAGGGAAUAUGCCUCCUAUGGAACAUGAUGGGGAUGUUAUAGAACAGUCAAACAUAAGAAUUUCAUCUGCUGAAAAUAAAAGUGCUCCAGACAAUGAAACAUCCAAAUCUGCUAAUCAAGAUACCUGUAGUCCUUUUGCAGGGAUGCUCUUUGGAGGUGAAGAUCGAGAACUUAUUCAGAGAAGGAAAGAGAAAUACAGACUAGAACUGUUGGAACAAAUGGCUGAGCAACAGAGGAACAAGAGACGAGAAAAAGAUUUAGAACUCAGGGUUGCAGCGUCUGGAGCACAAGACCCUGAGAAAUCGCCUGAUAGACUAAAGCAGUUUAGUGUGGCACCAAGACACUUUGAAGAGAUGAUACCACCUGAAAGACCCAGAAUAGCUUUCCAGACACCUCUCCCUCCUUUAUCUGCCCCAUCUGUCCCACCCAUCCCAUCAGUUCAUCCUGUUCCUUCUCAAAAUGAAGAUUUGCGCAGUGGACUCAGCAGCGCCCUUGGUGAAAUGGUGUCUCCCAGGAUUGCACCUCUGCCUCCACCUCCCCUACUACCACCUUUGGCUACUAACUAUCGAACUCCUUAUGAUGAUGCAUACUAUUUUUAUGGGUCCAGGAAUACUUUCGAUCCCAGUCUUGCUUAUUAUGGUUCAGGAAUGAUGGGCGUACAGCCUGCAGCUUAUGUUAGUGCUCCUGUCACCCACCAACUAGCACAACCUGUUGUGAAUACGGUUGGACAGAAUGAACUGAAGAUUACAAGUGAUCAAGUGAUAAAUUCAGGAUUGAUUUUUGAAGAUAAACCGAAACCUUCCAAACAGUCACUUCAGUCUUACCAAGAGGCUUUGCAGCAGCAGAUUCGGGAAAGAGAAGAAAGAAGGAAGAAAGAACGUGAAGAAAAAGAAGAAUAUGAAGCUAAAUUAGAAGCUGAAAUGAGAACAUAUAAUCCCUGGGGAAAAGGUGGAGGUGGUGCUCCUCUCAGGGAUGCAAAAGGAAAUCUGAUAACUGAUUUGAAUAGGAUGCACAGACAAAAUAUAGAUGCCUACCAUAACCCAGAUGCAAGAACAUAUGAAGAUAAAAGGGCUGUUGUAUCUCUAGACCCAAAUUUAGCCACUUCAAAUGCUGAGAACCUAGAAGAUGCUGCAAAUAAAAGCUCAGGUCAUAUGCAAACACAGAGCUCUCCUUUUGCUCGGGGAAAUGUAUUUGGUGAGCCUCCAACUGAACUUCAGAUUAAACAGCAAGAAUUAUACAAGAAUUUUCUUCGUUUCCAGAUUGAGGAAAAGAAACAAAGAGAGGAAGCAGAGCGAGAGAGACUGAGAAUUGCAGAAGAAAAAGAAGAAAGACGGCUUGCAGAACAGAGGGCACGAAUUCAGCAGGAGUAUGAAGAGGAACAGGAAAAGAAAAGAGAGAAAGAGGAGGAGCAAAGGCUAAAAAAUGAAGAGCAUAUUCGGUUAGCUGAAGAAAGACAAAAAGAAGCAGAAAGAAAGAAGAAAGAAGAAGAAGAAAAAUAUAACCUGCAACUUCAGCACUACUGUGAAAGAGACAAUUUGAUUGGGGAAGAAACAAAGCACAUGAGACAGCCUUCUCCUAUAGUUCCUGCUCUUCAGAACAAAAUUGCAAGCAAACUCCAAAGACCUCCUUCAGUUGACAGCAUCAUACGUUCCUUUAUUCAUGAAAGUUCCAUGUCCAGGGCACAGUCACCCCCGGUACCUGCCAGGAAAAAUCAGCUCCGUGCAGAAGAGGAGAAAAAAAAUGUAAUUAUGGAAUUAUCAGAAAUGAGAAAACAGCUUCGUAGUGAAGAGAGGCGUCUACAAGAGCGAUUGCUACACAUGGACAGUGAUGAUGAAAUUCCUAUCAGGAAAAAGGAAAGGAAUCCCAUGGAUAUAUUUGAUAUGGCUAGACAUCGGUUGCAAGCUCCUGUCAGAAGACAGUCCCCUAAGGGCUUAGACGCUGCCACUUUUCAGAAUGUUCAUGAUUUUAAUGAGCUGAAAGAUAGAGAUUCAGAAACACGAGUUGAUCUGAAAUUUAUGUACCUGGAUCCUCCAAGAGAUCAUCACACCUUAGAGAUUCAGCAGCAAGCCCUGCUAAGAGAGCAGCAGAAGAGGCUGAACAGAAUAAAAAUGCAGGAAGGUGCCAAAGUUGACUUAGAUGCCAUCCCAAGUGCUAAAGUACGAGAGCAAAGAAUGCCCAGAGAUGACACUAGUGAUUUCUUGAAAAACUCAUUAUUGGAAUCUGAUAGUGCUUUUAUUGGGGCUUACGGUGAGACAUAUCCUGCCAUUGAAGAUGACGUCCUCCCUCCACCAUCACAGUUGCCCUCUGCACGGGAGCGCAGGAGGAACAAAUGGAAAGGACUAGACAUUGAUAGCAGUCGUCCUAAUGUAGCACCAGAUGGUCUCUCUCUAAAAUCUAUAUCCAGUGUAAAUGUUGAUGAGCUUAGAGUGAGAAAUGAGGAACGAAUGCGAAGACUGAAUGAAUUUCACAAUAAACCUAUUAAUACAGAUGAUGAGAGUUCACUGGUUGACCCUGAUGACAUCAUGAAACACAUAGGGGAUGACGGAUCAAACUCUGUAGCAACUGAGCCCUGGCUCCGCCCUGGCACUUCAGAAACGCUGAAACGUUUCAUGGCAGAGCAGCUGAACCAGGAGCAGCAGCAGAUUCCUGGAAAACCAGGCACUUUCACUUGGCAGGGCCUGUCGACUGCACAUGGUUAAAAUAAACCUGUACUGGACCCAGUAGUGCCUUUUAAGGUGAAAGGAAUGGUAAAUCUGUACCUUUAAUAUGUCCUACUUUUGGCCCCUACCUGAAAGUUACUUUUUUUCCAUCAUCUGUAUAUAAAAUUAUUUUUAUCAUGAUGUAUAUUAUGUACAUAAAUAAAAGGCCAUGAUUAUUGAUUUAUAUAAUAGAAUUGUAUAGAUUAUUUUUGCACAGUUUUGUCAUAAAUUAGGGUGGUAAUGAACUGGAUUGAACUACUAUAUGUGCAUUAUAUUGAAUUCUGCUUGUCAUUAAGAUAAGGUGAAUAAGUGUCUUAAACGUCCUGUAAAACCGGACUCCCCUUUGUUACAUGCACAUUUUCCAUUGUUACCUCGAUGCAAAAGAAUUCAUUUAGUAGGUACAUCUAUUGUAGCUGUGAUUAUUCCAGUUUCUGUGUGAUGCAAUCAAAUGUCCUAUUAAUUAAUUAUUAUUUCAUGUCAUUUGUAGCUACUGAUACAGCAGAAAUGAAGGGAACUGUAAUUACUUGUAUUUUUGUAAGCCAUACGUUAAAUGUUUGUUACAUCAUCUUUCUGCUUCUAUUUUUAUGCCAAUGAAGGCAUUUGUCUUGUUACUAAUUACAUGAUGUAACUACUUCUUGAUAUAAAUAAAUUUUUAUUUUAAUUACUAAAAUCUUUUUAACUACUAUGGAGCUUUCUAGACUAGUUUUCUAGAGGUUGAAUAGAGGUGGGGACACCCGGGAGUCAAGGACAGAGAGACUGGAGUCUUCUUCUUCCACCAUGGAACCUUGGAUAAGUGAGUCCAUGUGAGUUUUCUAAUCACUCAGUAAGUGAUACUUCUAAAAAAGGAAAGAGUCAUUCAAAUAAUUGUGACAUUCUGACUCAGAUUAGAAUCUCAGAACCAUGACAGCUGAGAACAUCCCCAGGCACUGCUUCUCUCUCUAAUAAUACUUCCUCUGAUGUAAUUAACGGUUGGUAGACAAUAUCAGACAAAUUUGCCACAAUUAAAUUACUGAUAUUUUGA